GGUAGAGAAGACUACUGUGGGGUUUCAACAUGGCUAAAGUUACCAGAAAGUUGAAGGGAUCUAGCAAAGUUAUGGAGCAAUCAAACCCAAGCACAGAACAAUUAAUCUCAAGCACAAAAGGGAAGAACAAGAUGAAGAAAUCCUGUCAACCCAGGGCCAGAAAAGGGGGCAAGGUGAAGAAGAUACAGAGGGUGAUAAAACGACUGCUUCAUGGGAGUUCAAGAAAAAAAUCGUCUAGUACUAGUACAGAAAUUCCACAAAAGGUAAAAAGAGUGAAAAGAGCCAAGAAUCGGCCACUAGCAAAGAUUGAGUAGGAGCCAAAGCACUCAGGCCAGGCCCAAGAUGCUGUAAAAAAAAAUGACACUCCUACAAGAUACAACAGCAUAAUGAAACAGCGAUGGUGGUAAUUAAAACAAAAUCAACAUGUUAUGAAAAACCCUUUA